GUCACUCGACUACCAAGAUGGCGGCCCCCGGGAGCUGUGCUCUAUGGAGCUAUUGCGGCCGUGGGUGGUCGCGGGCGAUGCGGGGCUGCCAGCUCCUCGGGCUUCGUAGCUCUUGGCCCGGGGACCUACUAAGUGCUCGGCUCUUGUCCCAAGAGAAGCGGGCAGCGGAAACGCACUUUGGGUUUGAGACUGUGUCGGAAGAGGAGAAGGGGGGCAAAGAACUCCUUUAAUGUGAAAGUUUUUGCUGGCAUCACUUCUUCUGGGACAUCUUCAACCUUUUUGUCACAGCUCCAUUUCUUGUUCAUGUUGUCUAUCAGGUGUUUGAAAGUGUGGCUAAGAAGUAUGAUGUGAUGAAUGAUAUGAUGAGUCUUGGUAUCCAUCGUGUUUGGAAGGAUUUGCUGCUCUGGAAGAUGCACCCGCUUCCUGGGACCCAGCUGCUUGAUGUUGCUGGAGGCACAGGUGACAUUGCAUUCCGGUUCCUUAAUUAUGUUCAGUCCCAGCAUCAGAGAAAACAGAAGAGGCAGUUAAGGGCCCAACAAAAUUUAUCCUGGGAAGAAAUUGCCAAAGAGUACCAGAAUGAAGAAGAUUCCUUGGGCGGGUCUCGUGUCGUGGUGUGUGACAUCAACAAGGAGAUGCUAAAGGUUGGAAAGCAGAAAGCCUUGGCUCAAGGAUACAGAGCUGGACUUGCAUGGGUAUUAGGAGAUGCUGAAGAACUGCCCUUUGAUGAUGACAAGUUUGAUAUUUACACCAUUGCCUUUGGGAUCCGGAAUGUCACACACAUUGAUCAGGCACUCCAGGAAGCUCAUCGGGUGCUGAAACCAGGAGGACGGUUUCUCUGUCUGGAAUUUAGCCAAGUGAACAAUCCCCUCAUAUCCAGGCUUUAUGAUCUAUAUAGCUUCCAGGUCAUCCCUGUCCUGGGAGAGGUCAUCGCUGGAGACUGGAAGUCCUAUCAGUACCUUGUAGAGAGUAUCCGAAGGUUUCCGUCUCAGGAAGAGUUCAAGGACAUGAUAGAAGAUGCAGGCUUUCACAAGGUGACUUACGAAAGUCUAACAUCAGGCAUUGUGGCCAUUCAUUCUGGCUUCAAACUUUAAUUCCUUUCCUAUCAUGGAGCAUGAACCAGUCAUAUCCUGUUGAAAGCCUGGAACUGAAGGAUAAUCUGGCAAAUGAGACAGCAGCAGAGCAUCUCCUCUUAAGGAUACGUGCCUUGGACUCAUGUUUGAAUCGAACAGUCUCAAAGUGGAAGAACAAAUUCUUGUCACUUUUUUACAGCUUUCUUUGGAGCUGCUUCAGUCCAUCUCCCAGAGGCAUUUGGUCUGUAUCUUUGCUCAACUGCUAAUUUCUCUUGGCUGUAGGGUGUGUGGUUAAGGUACAACCACCCCUAAAGCUCAGUUUUGAAGUGAGUGUAUUUAUAGCUUCUCUGCUGGUGCUGCCUUCUAGAGGGAUGAUAGAUCAUUUGAACCCAAUGACAAUUUUUAACCAGAAAAUUUAAUUGUACCUGAAUCAACCUUUCAGCCUAGGACGAAGUCUAGGCCCAAGUCAGAGUAUUAAUGAUCAUGAGAAUUGUGUGCUGAACCAGUAAACGAGUUUACCUUUUGA